GUGCGGUGCCGGGAGGGCGGCUGGGCAGGCGGCAGGAUGCUGCGCGCCGCCCUGUCCCUGCUCGCGCUGCCCCUGGCGGGGGCGGCCGAAGAGCCCACCCAGAAGCCAGAGUCCCCGGGCGAGCCUCCCCCAGGCUUAGAGCUCUUCCGCUGGCAGUGGCACGAGGUGGAGGCGCCCUACCUGGUGGCCCUGUGGAUCCUGGUGGCCAGUCUGGCCAAAAUCGUGUUUCACCUGUCUCGGAAAGUAACAUCUCUGGUCCCUGAGAGCUGCCUGCUGAUUUUGCUGGGCCUGGUGCUAGGGGGAAUUGUUUUGGCUGUGGCCAAGAAAGCUGAGUACCAGCUGGAGCCAGGCACCUUCUUCCUCUUCCUGCUGCCUCCUAUUGUGUUGGACUCAGGCUAUUUCAUGCCUAGCAGGCUGUUCUUUGACAACUUGGGUGCCAUCCUCACCUAUGCCGUGGUAGGCACACUCUGGAAUGCCUUCACAACAGGCGCUGCCCUCUGGGGCUUGCAGCAGGCUGGACUUGUAGCCCCUAGGGUGCAGGCUGGCUUACUGGACUUCCUGCUGUUUGGGAGCCUCAUCUCGGCGGUGGACCCCGUGGCCGUGCUAGCUGUCUUUGAGGAGGUGCACGUCAAUGAGACUCUCUUUAUCAUCGUCUUUGGCGAGUCCCUGCUCAACGAUGCUGUCACCGUGGUGCUGUACAAGGUCUGCAACUCCUUUGUGGAGAUGGGCUCUGCCAAUGUGCAGGCCACUGACUACCUGAAGGGAGUCGCCUCCCUGUUUGUGGUCAGUCUGGGCGGGGCAGCCGUGGGCUUAGUCUUUGCCUUCCUCCUGGCCCUGACCACACGCUUCACCAAGCGGGUCCGCAUCAUCGAGCCGCUGCUGGUCUUCCUCCUCGCCUACGCAGCCUACCUCACUGCUGAAAUGGCCUCGCUCUCCGCCAUUCUUGCGGUGACCAUGUGUGGCCUGGGCUGUAAGAAGUACGUGGAGGCCAACAUCUCCCAUAAGUCACGCACAACUGUCAAAUAUACAAUGAAGACUCUAGCCAGCUGUGCUGAGACCGUGAUCUUCAUGCUGCUUGGCAUCUCAGCCGUGGACUCUUCUAAGUGGGCCUGGGAUUCUGGGCUGGUGCUGGGCACCCUCAUCUUCAUCCUGUUCUUCCGAGCCCUCGGCGUAGUCCUGCAGACCUGGGUGCUGAAUCAGUUCCGGCUAGUCCCUCUGGACAAGAUUGACCAAGUGGUGAUGUCCUAUGGGGGCCUGCGGGGGGCUGUGGCCUUUGCUCUCGUCAUCCUACUGGAUAGGACCAAGGUCCCUGCCAAGGACUACUUUGUAGCCACCACUAUUGUAGUGGUCUUCUUCACAGUCAUCGUGCAGGGCUUGACCAUCAAGCCACUGGUCAAAUGGCUGAAGGUGAAGAGGAGUGAGCAUCACAAACCCACCCUGAACCAGGAGCUGCAUGAACACACUUUUGACCACAUUCUGGCUGCAGUGGAGGACGUUGUGGGGCACCAUGGCUACCACUACUGGAGGGACAGGUGGGAGCAGUUUGACAAGAAAUACCUGAGUCAGCUGCUGAUGCGACGAUCAGCCUACCGCAUCCGGGACCAGAUCUGGGAUGUGUACUACAGGCUUAACAUCCGGGAUGCCAUCAGCUUUGUGGACCAGGGAGGCCACGUCUUGUCUUCCACAGGUCUCACUCUGCCUUCUAUGCCCAGCCGCAAUUCUGUGGCAGAAACUUCUGUCACCAACCUGCUGAGGGAGAGUGGCAGUGGAGCGUGUCUGGAUCUGCAGGUGAUUGACACAGUACGCAGCGGCCGGGAUCGUGAGGAUGCUGUGAUGCAUCAUCUGCUCUGCGGAGGCCUCUACAAGCCGCGCCGUAGGUACAAAGCCAGCUGCAGUCGCCACUUCAUCUCAGAGGAUGCGCAGGAGCGGCAGGACAAGGAGGUCUUCCAGCAGAACAUGAAGCGGCGGCUGGAGUCCUUUAAGUCCACCAAGCACAACAUCUGCUUCACCAAGAGCAAGCCACGACCCCGCAAGACUGGCCGCAGGAAGAAGGAUGGUGUGGCGAAUGCUGAGGCUACAAAUGGGAAACAUCGAGGCCUGGGCUUUCAGGACACAGCUGCUGUGAUAUUAACCGUGGAGUCUGAGGAGGAGGAGGAGGAGAGCGACAGUUCAGAGACAGAGAAGGAGGACGAUGAGGGGAUCAUCUUUGUGGCUCGUGCCACCAGUGAGGUUCUCCAAGAGGGCAAGGUCUCAGGAAGCCUUGAGGUGUGCCCAAGCCCACGAAUCAUUCCCCCCUCCCCAACCUGUGCAGAAAAGGAGCUCCCCUGGAAGAGUGGGCAGGGGGACCUGGCAGUGUACGUGUCCUCGGAAACCACCAAGAUUGUGCCUGUGGACAUGCAGACGGGUUGGAACCAGAGCAUCUCAUCCCUGGAGAGCCUAGCGUCCCCUCCCUGUAACCAGGCCCCAAUUCUGACCUGCCUGCCUCCCCAUCCACGGGGCACUGAAGAGCCCCAGGUCCCUCUCCACCUACCUUCUGAUCCACGCUCUAGCUUCGCCUUCCCACCGAGCCUGGCCAAGGCUGGCCGCUCUCGCAGUGAGAGCAGCGCUGACCUCCCCCAGCAGCAGGAGCUGCAGCCCCUCAUGGGCCACAAGGACCACACCCAUCUCAGCCCAGGCACCGCUACCUCCCACUGGUGCAUCCAGUUCAACAGAGGCAGCCGGCUGUAGCUCAAGGCCUCGGGGAGGAGCAGGAGGUGGAAUCCCUGUGGGAAGUGCUCCCUGGGUGAUGGGUAGAGCCCUCGAAACUUGACAUGGGGCCAGAAGGGCCUGGGUUGAAGUAGUAAUUGGGCUUCCUUGGAGCUAGUCAGAGGGGUCACCUAAGCUGGUCCUCACAGGGGCCUUUCUCACCACCUCCCUGCUCCUAACCCCUGCCACUUUCUGUUUCAUUAAGGCCUCUACUCUGGCUCAGGACCCAGUCCAGGCCUUCUACGGGCUAGGCCCAGAGACUUGGGUUGCUGGUCCCCCUUCCCUAGUGGGUUUUCCCGGGGACUCUAUAGGCAGCUGCUCCUGCCCGCAAAGCAAGAGCAUCAUUCCUAUUCUUCAGUGGAUGCCAGCCUUCCCUGCCCCAACUCCCUCCCCAGCACUGGGUCAGUGGUGUCCUGGCAGUGAGGCUCCGUGAGGGGCUGGCCCUUAGAGGAACUGGGGUGGGAGGUGGGGCAGGCCUCACCCUUGGGCUUUGCUGCCCUGUUGGGUCAGCUACCCAUAGUCCAUUUUUUUAGGGCAGUGGGAACCUCUGCCUCCACUUCCUGCUUUAGCCCCUUCCCUUUGCUGCCAGGUAUUGGGGUAAUAUUUCCUCCUUUUCCAAGACCAAGGCCAAGAGGCUGGGCCAGGCUUCAGUUCAGGCCUGUUGCUUAACUGGGGUCACCCUGGGAUCUGCUGCUCUGGGUCUAAGUCUAGACCUUUCUGAUCCUUGGGUCUGGGUUUUUUGAGGAGGGGACAUAGUGGCCUCUGGGCUGCCAUGUCACCACCUGAACAUUCCCCAAACAGAGAAGGAACCCAGCAUCUCAGGGCCACUGCUCCAUUGCUCUGGGGGCUGGGAUGCCUGGCUAAGCAGGGGCUGACAGGGUGGCAGGUGACUUUCUAGGGAUCAGCACCUGCCCUGUGUUUUGUACCUUGAACCUAAGAUAUAUUAAACAUCUCUCAGAUGGA